AGAUGCCUCACCUCUAGGGGAUGCUGAUUCUGGGAUGCCUUUUUCGUCUCCUAGGCUCCUCAAGGCCAACUGCGCUGGGAAGAGGGGGUGUCCAACAGCAGGAGGGCUGUUUUUUUGAACUACAAUUUGCCAGCAUACAGCAGAGCAGCAAGAAGAUAACAGGGCGGGGGGCACGGGAUUAGCCCAAACAAAACACACUCAAGAACGCGAGUCUGUGGUUCAACACGAGGCAGAAAACAGCUGGGCCGGGUGCGGGGCUUCUCCCUCGCGUGUAUCCGCUCACUGCACUCGCUGCCCUGGCCGCGGGCGCCGCGCAGGGUGCUGAUGUCCAGGAGGGAUCUAGACCUCCCGCGGCGCUCGGGCUAGUGGACGCAGGUGGUCCCAAAUGCUGGGACCAAGCUAGGAACCAAGCGGAAGCUCGGAUUGCUCGGCAUCGGGCCUCGUCGUUAUUCUACCGUGAGGGAAACUGAGACCGAGGGCACGGCAGGGAGUCGCCCGCCGUCUCACCAGCGUGAGGGGUUGCGCCGGGCCCCGAAAACUGGUUUGCGCCGCCCGGCAUCGGGAUCCGGGACCUCUGCCCGCCGGGCGCUGCCUGCGCGUUCCUGGAACUGGGCUGGGCGGAGAAAUCAGGGCCCGCAGAGAGGCAUUCCUGCCGCCUUCCCCGCCGCCCGGGGCCGCAGGGGGGCCUGGCCAAGGCUUCCAGCACAGAGGAGCUUCGGGGAGGCUGGAUUGCGCCUGUGUCUAAAAAUAAACAGGUUCCUGCGUGAAGACCAGCUGGGAGCCCACUGCCUGCUGCCACCUCCAACUCCGGCCCCCUCACCAUGCACUCCCUGGACGAGCCGCUCGACCUGAAGCUGAGUAUCACCAAGCUCCGGGCGGCAAGAGAGAAGCGGGAGAGGACGCUGGGUGUGGUCCGGCCCCGUGCUCUGCACAGGGAGCUGGGCCUGGUGGAUGACAGCCCCACACCUGGCUCUCCAGGCUCCCCGCCCUCAGGCUUCCUGCUGAACUCCAAGUUCCCCGAGAAGGUGGAGGGACGCUUUUCAGCAGCCCCUCUCGUGGACCUCAGCCUGUCACCACCAUCUGGGCUGGACUCCCCCAAUGGCAGCAGCUCGCUGUCCCCCGAGCGCCAGGGCAACGGGGACCUGCCUCCAGUGCCCAGUGCCUCGGACUUCCAGCCACUGCGCUAUUUGGAUGGUGUCCCCAGCUCCUUCCAGUUCUUCCUGCCCCUCGGCUCCGGGGGGGCCCUGCACCUGCCUGCCUCCUCCUUCCUUACCCCUCCCAAGGACAAGUGCCUCUCGCCAGACCUGCCCCUGCCCAAGCAGCUGGUGUGUCGCUGGGCCAAGUGUAACCAGCUCUUUGAGCUCCUGCAAGACCUGGUGGACCAUGUCAACGAUUACCAUGUCAAGCCCGAGAAGGAUGCGGGGUACUGCUGCCACUGGGAGGGCUGCGCCCGCCAUGGCCGAGGUUUCAACGCCAGGUACAAGAUGCUCAUCCACAUCCGCACACACACCAACGAGAAGCCACACCGCUGUCCGACCUGCAGCAAGAGCUUCUCCCGCCUGGAGAACCUGAAGAUCCACAACCGGUCGCACACAGGUGAGAAGCCCUACGUCUGCCCCUACGAGGGCUGCAACAAGCGCUAUUCCAACUCCAGUGACCGCUUUAAGCACACGCGCACCCACUAUGUGGACAAGCCCUACUACUGCAAGAUGCCCGGCUGCCACAAGCGCUACACGGACCCCAGCUCACUGCGCAAGCACAUCAAGGCCCAUGGCCACUUUGUGUCCCACGAGCAGCAAGAGCUCCUGCAGCUGCGCCCACCCCCCAAGCCGCCACUGCCCGCCCCCGACGGCGGCCCCUAUGUCAGUGGGGCCCAGAUCAUCAUCCCCAACCCAGCUGCCCUCUUUGGAGGCCCUGGCCUGCCCGGCUUACCCCUACCCCUGGCCCCCGGCCCCCUUGACCUCAGUGCCCUGGCCUGUGGCAACGGUGGGGGCAGUGGGGGUGGGGGGGGCAUGGGCCCUGGGCUGCCAGGCCCCGUCCUGCCUCUCAAUCUGGCCAAGAACCCGCUGCUGCCCUCGCCCUUUGGGGCUGGCGGACUGGGCUUGCCUGUGGUCUCCCUCCUUGCUGGCGCAGCUGGUGGCAAGGCCGAGGGGGAGAAGGGGCGUGGGUCGGUGCCCACCAGGGCCCUGGGCAUGGAGGGCCACAAGACGCCCCUUGAAAGGACGGAGAGCAGCUGCUCCCGGCCAAGCCCCGAUGGACUCCCCCUGCUGCCAGGCACCGUGCUGGACCUGUCCACGGGCGUCAACUCAGCUGCCAGCAGCCCAGAGGCGUUGGCCCCUGGCUGGGUGGUCAUCCCGCCGGGCUCGGUGCUGCUCAAACCGGCUGUGGUGAACUGAGCCCAUCCUGCGGACAGUUGUGGUGCCCCCCCGGCAGCUCCCGGCACUGCCCCCGACGAACGGAAACUCUUCUGUGAAAUAGCAAUAAUGUCCUACUGCCCGGGCAGCCCCAGCCCAGCCCGCCGGGAGCAAGGAUGGUGCUAGGUCAUUCAUGGCUGGCCUCCCAGCCCCCGGGUGGGGACCUGGCCUGUCAUGCAGGGAGAGCUGUGCUCCUGGGUGCUGAAGCCUCGCUCCUGUCUGUCCCCCACCACCUGGCCCUCAGCUUCUGAGAGGCUUUCCCCUGCCCGACCUCCUCCCGUUUCCCUCUCCCACCCUGGCACCUCCCUCACCUAGUGACCACCCAUGGCAAGUUGCCCUCUCCCAGCAGAGGGGGUGGGUGGGGUGGCAUCUGCCCUCCCUGCUAGCACCAGGCUCCCCCUUCCUGAGAGGAGCCCCCAGGGACCAGAGGCCUGCCCUUCCCUCCUAGGCUUACCCAGCCCCUGCCCUGGGGGCUCCUUGGACCCCUUUCCCUCUGACCCUGCCUCCAGAGGGAAAGCAAGACAGAUGCAGGCCCCUGCAAAGCCCCAGGUAGAAGCAUGCCCCCCAGGACAAGGCGCCUCCCACUAGUUAGGAGGAGGCCCGCUCUGCAGCCGCCGUCCUCACCCCAGGCCAGGCCUGCAGUACCAGACGGGAUAGCUGGCCACUCCACCCCUGCACCCCAGGGUCUCCUCCCUCUACCUUUUGGGGCACCCUGGGAGCGUGGGAAGCAGGUCCGAGGGCCCCUGAGCUGGCAAGGGGAGGUGCCAGGCCAGCUGUGGUGCCAAGAUACUGAGUGACCUGGGCCCUGGCUCAGGGAGCAUGUGGGGCCAGGCCCAGCGCCCCGUCUUCCUCCUUCUACCCCCGCUGGGCCUGGCCUGGGCAGCGCCCCCUGCAGAGGCCUUUGGGUCCUUGGUCCUGUAACAGGAAGGGGGAGGCUGGCUGGGGACGACCGACCACAGGCUGGGACACAGCUCCUGGUCUGGGGGCUCCAAGUGACAGCAUGCAGGGGAGGGGGCUCCCAGUCAGUGCUGUGUUGGGAGCUUUCUGGAGGCUGUGGACUGAAGGCCUUGAGGGAAGCAGUGGCUGGAGGAGGGUGCUGGACCCAUGACACGUUGCUUCCUCUGGCUUUUCCCUGCUGGGCCGCUUUCUCAGAGGCACUUCCCCACCCCUAACACCCAGUGGGCCCCCCCAGGUUCUGUGCCACUCAGAGGGACCCUGGCAGGGGCCAGAACCACUUAAGGGUGGUGCUGGAGGGCCUUGUGCCCCAGUCCCAUCCCAGGACGCCCUGAGGGAUGGACGCAGCCAUGCACCCCCCAUCUGGGGCCUCUCCCUGCUCCCUCUCCCACCUGGCAGCUGGGAGUUCUGGCUUCUAGGCCUGCCCUGUCACCAGGCCUCUGAGUGGCCAGGCCCUUCCACCUCCCCAUCUGUAAAACGAGGCAGCUGCCCGGACAGCCUUGGGGUCCUUAGUGGCCCUGCAGGUCCUCUGGCAGCUCUGCUGACCCCACCCUCUCCCGGACUGCCCUUCUGUCCCAGAGGGGUCACCCUGACCCGGCCCACCUUGCCACUGGGCUUUGGACUCCAGCCCUGACAGGGCCCAGCCACACUGGCUCUGCCCCUCGAAGGGGCUAUGAGCAAGGUAGGAGGGAGCUGGUCUCCUUUCUUCGGGCCCCACCCAGGCCCUGAGCACCCCCCACCCCUGUGAGGGCCCCAGGCCUUAAGUCCCUGGCGGGGUCAUGGGUUUGCGACUUGAGCAGAGCGGAGGAACAGGGCACUGGAAGGCCGACGAGCUCAGCAUGCGACUCGGUGACGGACCAGGCUCGGCAGGGCCGGUGUACUUUUUGUGGUUGUCAUUGGUGUGUUGUUGCACAUUCCAGGACGUCAGUAUUUUAACAGGUUCUAAGUGCCUUUCUAUCGUAGCUUAUGUUUUCCUCCUCUUGGCUCCAUUGCUGUUAGCAUAGAGUUUUAAAAAAAGAGAUAAGCUAAUGACUAUAACAAUAUAUUCCUCCAUGGGAGAGGAAGUUUAUAAAGAAACAAUAAAAGUGAGUUGCAAAGA